GCAGCGCGCCGGGAGUGUGGCGUUCUGUGAAGAGUUCGGUGCUAACCUCCCUCACGCGGCGGUGGCUGCCGGGACCCUAGCAGGUUUCAGCUGGAGCGGCGGCGGCGGCAACAUGGCAGAGACCGCGGCCGGAGUGGGCCGCUUCAAGACCAACUAUGCUGUGGAGCGCAAAAUUGAGCCUUUCUACAAGGGCGGAAAAGCACAGCUGGACCAGACUGGCCAGCACCUCUUCUGCGUCUGUGGCACCAGAGUCAACAUUCUGGAAGUGGCCUCGGGGGCCGUGCUGCGGAGUCUGGAGCAGGAGGACCAGGAGGACAUCACUGCCUUUGACCUCAGCCCUGACAACGAGGUGCUGGUGACAGCCAGUCGGGCAUUGCUGCUGGCUCAGUGGGCCUGGCAAGAGGGCAGCGUUACCCGCCUGUGGAAGGCGAUACACACGGCCCCCGUGGCCACCAUGGCCUUCGACCCCACCUCCACUCUGCUAGCCACAGGUGGCUGUGAUGGGGCCGUGCGCGUCUGGGACAUCGUGCGGCACUACGGGACACACCACUUCCGAGGCUCGCCCGGUGUCGUGCACCUAGUGGCCUUCCACCCGGACCCUACACGCCUGCUGCUCUUCUCCUCGGCCACGGAUGCCGCCAUCCGCGUGUGGUCACUGCAGGACCGGUCAUGCCUGGCUGUGCUGACUGCCCACUACAGCGCCGUCACCUCACUGGCCUUCAGCGCCGACGGCCACACCAUGCUCAGCUCCGGCCGUGACAAGAUAUGUAUCAUCUGGGACCUUCAGAGCUGCCAGGCCACGAGGACCGUGCCUGUGUUUGAGAGCGUGGAGGCUGCUGUGCUGUUGCCAGAGGAGCCAGUGUCCCAGCUGGGUGUGAAGUCCCCAGGGCUGUACUUUCUGACAGCUGGCGACCAAGGCACUCUGCGCGUGUGGGAGGCAGCUUCUGGGCAGUGUGUGUACACGCAGGCCCAGCCGCCGGGCCCUGGGCAGGAGCUGACCCACUGCACCCUGGCACACACCGCCGGCGUGGUCCUCACCGCCACCGCCGACCACAACCUGUUGCUCUACGAGGCUCGCUCCCUGCGGCUGCAGAAACAGUUCGCUGGCUACAGUGAGGAGGUUUUGGAUGUCCGGUUUCUUGGGCCCGAGGACUCCCACGUUGUCGUGGCCUCCAAUAGCCCCUGCCUAAAAGUGUUUGAGCUGCAGACGUCAGCCUGCCAGAUCCUCCACGGCCACACGGAUAUCGUCCUGGCCCUGGAUGUGUUCCGGAAGGGGUGGCUCUUUGCCAGCUGUGCCAAGGAUCAGAGCGUCCGUAUCUGGAGAAUGAACAAGGCUGGCCAGGUGAUGUGCGUGGCUCAGGGUUCCGGUCACACACACAGUGUGGGCACCGUCUGCUGCUCUAGGCUGAAGGAGUCCUUCCUGGUGACAGGCAGCCAGGACUGCACUGUGAAGCUGUGGCCUCUUCCCAAAGCCUUGCUGUCCAAGAACACAGCCCCAGACAACGGCCCUAUCCUCCUGCAGGCCCAGACCACUCAGCGCUGCCAUGAUAAGGACAUCAACAGCGUGGCUAUUGCCCCCAACGACAAGCUGCUGGCCACAGGCUCACAGGACCGCACGGCCAAGCUCUGGGCCCUGCCACAGUGCCAGCUGCUGGGUGUCUUCUCAGGCCACCGGCGUGGCCUCUGGUGCGUCCAGUUCUCUCCCAUGGACCAGGUGCUGGCCACGGCCUCAGCUGAUGGCACCAUCAAGCUCUGGGCACUCCAGGACUUCAGCUGUCUCAAGACAUUUGAGGGGCACGAUGCUUCUGUGCUGAAGGUGGCCUUUGUGAGCCGUGGCACGCAGCUGCUGUCCAGCGGUUCGGAUGGCCUCGUGAAGCUCUGGACCAUCAAGAACAACGAGUGUGUGCGGACGCUGGAUGCCCACGAGGACAAGGUCUGGGGGCUGCACUGCAGCCGGCUGGACGACCACGCCCUCACUGGGGCCAGUGACUCCCGAGUCAUCCUCUGGAAGGAUGUGACCGAGGCGGAGCAGGCAGAGGAGCAGGCCAGGCAAGAGGAGCAGGUGGUCAGGCAGCAAGAGCUGGACAACCUGCUGCAUGAGAAGCGGUACCUGCGGGCGCUGGGCCUGGCCAUCUCCCUGGAUCGGCCCCACACCGUGCUGACUGUCAUCCAGGCCAUCCGGAGGGACCCUGAGGCCUGCGAGAAGCUGGAAGCCACCAUGCUCCGACUGCGGCGCGACCAGAAAGAGGCCCUGCUGCGCUUCUGCGUCACGUGGAACACCAACUCGCGGCACUGCCACGAGGCCCAGGCCGUGCUGGGUGUGCUCUUGAGGCGAGAGGCCCCCGAGGAGCUGCUGGCCUACGAAGGCGUGCGGGCAGCGCUUGAGGCCCUGCUGCCCUACACUGAGCGGCACUUUCAGCGGCUCAGCAGGACCCUCCAGGCCGCCGCUUUCUUGGACUUCCUGUGGCACAACAUGAAGCUCCCUGUGCCGGCCGCCGCCCCCACCCCCUGGGAAACCCAUAAAGGCGCACUGCCCUAGCCGGUCCGGCCUCUCUCCAGUCCAUCCUGAACCCCUGGAAAACCCAUAAAGGCCGCUCUCCUGGCCGGCUCUGUCUCUCUGGACUGCAGUCCAGCCCCCCACCCUGGCCAACACCCUACCUAGCCAGCCAGAAGGGCACUGGAGCUGAUGGUCUCGGCCCUGCCACGCCCAUCCCGCACCCUGGCCUGGCAGAGAUCCAGCCCGCGGCUCCGCACGCUUAGACGGUGGGGGUCAUGCAGAACAAGCUUUACUCAGAGGAACAGCAAAUGGCCCCCUCCCAUCCCUGCUGGCCAGGGAGAUCCGCCCUCCCCGCUCCUCCCCAGCCCUGGGAUGGCGCGGUCCAUCCCCUCAUCGGGAUCCUCGCGCUCACUGCUCCGUCGUGGGGUGCGGCACAGAGUCCACGCACCCUCGAGGGCGGCCCUGGCGCCGUGGGCGCCGCUCCAGGGCCCUGCGUGUGACGGUGCAGCAGCGGCUCUGGAUGGCGCCCGGCGAAGGUCGGGUGGGCACGGUGGGGGGAGGGGCGGUGGCCUGGGAGGGUUCAGGGAAGCCCCGGGCCUCACCCGCCGGGUCGUCUCCUCCACGGAACCCCGUCCCGCUCAGGAGAGCGCCCAGCCCUUCCGGCCGCAGCAGCACCGCGGGGAGUAGGCCCGCCCGGUCGCCGUACCUGCGAGGGGCGGGGUGUGGUUAGGGCCCCGCCCGCCUCGGCUAGCCUGCCCUGCCCACGCCCGCUCCCGCGUACCUGCAUAGCCACCAGCCGCGGUCUGACGUUUCCAACACGCGCACGCGCGCCCCCGCGGGCACGGACAGCUCAUCUGCGCGGCUGCUCUCGUAGGCGCGGGAAGCACAGAACUGGGGACCUGGUGGGAGUGGGUGUUUGGAGUCACCGCGGGGCCACAGAGGACGAGGCCCGCCCGCACCCUUCUCCACAUUCUCCUUGCUUGAGUCUGCUGACGGCGGGGCCGCUCUAAGACCGGUUCGGGGCUUCCUCUAGGUGCGGAGACCAAGCACGGGCUCCUGGCCCGCCCUGCCCGCGGUGCUUCUGGCCCAGUCUUGCCACACGGUCAAGCCGCAGUGGUGGCGUGAGGGGUGGGGUUAGGCGCAUACCGCUGCUCCCUAGGGACGGGCCUCCCUCCCGGCCUUGGCCCGGGGCCGCCUCCUCCAGGUAGGGCGCUGGAAACCAGGCGGUCUGCCGGUCUUCGUUCUCCACCAGCCACCAGCCUGUGCGCAAGAAGCGGGCAGGGACUCAAAUCUCGAGGCUCCCUCGGGUCCAGGAGCAGAGGAGCAAAUCCCUGGGUUCUUGGGGGGCCCUACCUGAGGGGUGCCGCAGCAGCACGUCCAGGCUCUCCUGGGCCUGCGCCUGAAAAGGCCUAUCCCGCGUGUCCUGGGUACAGAAGGGCUGCAGGCAGCGCAGGCUCUGAGCCUCCAGACUGUGGAUGGAGAGGCGGCCCGCAGCGCGAGAAAGAGGCUGCUCCUCUGGGGUGGGCAGGAUCACCCGGCUGGGAAGGGCAGCCCGUACGAGUGAGAGGUAGGCGGAUGGGGAGGGUGAAACUGGGGGCGCCACCCCGGCAAGACCGCCAGCCUCCCACUCUCUGCCCCUAUUCGCUGGCUGUUCCCCCCCACCCUGGACCUCUCCCAGCUCCAAACGCCGCUGCAUGCUGGGAGUUUGGGGCGAGUCAGGCACCUGCCGGGUGGCAGCGCGGGCUCCAGGUCCAGGGGUUGCGGUGCGAAGAAGCCAGUGAUCGUCGGGCUCCGUGCCACGCGCUCUGCAGUCGCCAGCAGCCUCCGAGAAUAGGUUUCCAACAGCUGCAGGCGCGCCAGGCCGCGGCUCGUGCGCCCCACGCGUCCCAACAGUGGUGCAUCUUAAGGCACCACAAAAACGUACUGUGAUACGCCGCUUUGGGCUUCACUGGUCCCUGGCGCCCCCAGGCAAGCCACCGCCUUCCCCGCUCCCGUACCCAGGCUGGCCUGACCGAGAAGCUUUGGGAGAACGCGGUCAGAUCUCCGCAGCAGGCCCGCCUCCACCGGGAAGGUCUCCUUGAGGGUCUUCUGAGGGCGGGAACCAGGGCAUUGGUCUUCCAGAGCCCACUGUGCACCCUUGAGAGGGCGGGGUCCCUCACCCGGAUGGCAGGGGCUGGGAGCUUCAGCAGGGACGAAGGGCCUCCAGUGGGAGUCACUGAUGGGAGGCAGUCCAGUGGGAGGCAGCCGCGUGGGGAAGCCGCCACCGCGGCAUCAGGGUGGCCCAGGGUCACUCACCUUGAGCUGCCUGAAUUCGUCCCAACUCCUGCGCACGAAGGUGUCGCUGCCGUCUGACCAGCGCACAGAGAAGGCAAACGUCUGGGGGACAAAAAGUUGGGAGUGCCGUGGAGGUGCUGGUCCAGGCACCCCCUUCCUAUCCCUUGGGGCCACUAAGGACCCAGCCAGGUCUUACUUGGAGCCUCUUGAUCUGCACCAGGGCUGCCCCUUGCACUGAAACUGGGUAUCGGGGGCCUGCCAUGGCUGUGGCUUCCAGGCUGCAGAUUCCUGAAAUGGGCGAGGACCCUUCUGCCUCCCCGUGCUUGAGAGGGCUCUGGGGGACCCAGAAAACCCCCUGGGAUAGAAUCCUGGCAACACCUCAAGCCUGUGGGGUCCUUGUGGAGCCGCCCCAGCUGAGUCCUUUGCAGCUUUCUUGCUGUCCCCCAAGCCCACGAUCUGGGGGCAGGAGCACAGGGAUUGGGGGACUUCCAGGCAGAGCUGCUGGGAGGAAGAAGAAGAAUGAGCUUUCCAGCCCUGGAGGCGUGCAAGACUGAAGAAGGGGCGAAGGGUAGGCGGGACUGCUGCCUGGGGCCCUCCUGCCUGCCUCUGGCCACAGGAGGAGGGAGGAGAAGGCAGGGCUAAUCAAAGCGCCACCUGUCCUGCCCACCUCUCUGGAUUCCCCUACCCUGUGAGGUAAUUGCCCUGCCAGGGUGCGCCCAACAACUUUGAACUGGCCUGGGGAUUUCUGUGCAGAACCAAGGACUCAGUGCUUACAGCUUUAAGUGCUUUGUCUGACUUAAUCCUAAUGCUGGAGGAAAGGUCUCUUAAUGUCCCCAACUCAUAGAGGAGGAAAUGUGUGUUAAAUGCGUAAUUAUUGUGAGCUGUUCUAUACAUGCUGGGGGAGGGGCAGACCUCACAGGCUCACCCCAGGGGUUCCCCUGCAGUGAGGAGACUUGGGGUAGGAGAAAGAGGGCCCAUCUGUGCAGUCACUGGCAUUUGGUGGGUGGGGGUGGUGGUCAGGGAAGUGGUCACUAGGGCUGUUUUGAGAACCACCUCUCAAUUCACGAUUUGCCAUGACUUACUGCAAACAUGGCCUGGGCAGAGGCUCGCCCAGGUGCCCCACCUCUCUGGCUGCUUCCUUAUAGUUCGGGCUUCGGAAGCCACAUUCAACCCUGGCACACAGUGGUUUUUCCUCGUGCUGGGGCCACCAGUUCUGUGUUGGGAUGCACCUACUCCAGCCCCUUCAGGGAGCAGUCAGCCUCUAAGGCAUCCCUCCAGGAAGCUGCCCUGGCUGCAACAAAGGGCCUUUGUGUGUCUGUCCCACCAGCACUCUCUCUCAUGCCCUCAAGCUGUCCCUGGUCUUGGCAUGGGCAAUGAACACCUGCUCACAUAGGGCUGAUUUGCAGGGUUCCCCCAGCCAGCUGUCACCUUCUCCCUGUCUCAGCUGAGGGCCCAGCUGACCUGGUGGGGUCCAGCGUGUGAACCCAGGGGAGACCUUGCUCCCCUGGAAGACAGGAGAAGCUGGGGAGGAUUUAUUCACAAGCAGAGGCCUAGAGGGAUUCUGAGGCCACCUGCCUACCCCAGCUGACAGCUCCUGCCCCACACCCCAUCAGCCCUGCAUGGUUUCCACUUUUUCCUCCCCUACCCUCUUUUCUUGCCUGAAUAGUACACCCCACCCUCCAUCUGUAUGCUCCUCACUUGCCCCUACAAAAUCCACUCCAAGGACAGACACAGUGCCUCACCUGUAAUCCAAGUACUUUGGGAGGCCGAGGCAGGGGGAUUGCUUGAGCUCAGGAGUUCGAGACCAGUCUGGGCAACAUGUUGAGACCUCCAUCUGUGCCCCCCAAAAAUACAAAAAUUAGCUGGGCGUGGUGGCGUGUGCCUGUAGUCUACUUGGGAGGCUGAGGUGGGAGAUCACUUGAGCCUAAGCAGUCGCGGCUGCAGUGAACAAGAUCGCGCCACUGCACUCCACCCUGGGUAACGGAACAAGACCCUGUCUCAAAAAAAAAAAA